GCCACCUACUCGGGCCUCUGGAGGAAGUGCUACUUCCUGGGCAUCGACCGGGACAUCGACACCCUCAUCCUGAAAGGUGAGCGGCGGGCGCACCCCGCGUCCCCGGCGCCCGCGCGUGGAGCGCAGCCCGCGGCUUCCCAGGGGCGCGCCGGUCCCCGCAGCCCCCUCCCAGCCGCGGCCCCGCGCCUGGGCAUUCUUGCAUCCUUCCCGCCGCCUCCAGUCUUUAUCUCUUCCCUUUCUUUCCCCACUGCCUCCCUUCUUCUCCCUCUCCUUGACUCUCUUCUUUCGUCCACAUCCUGCGCGUCCUUUCAAGUCCGUGCCGCACCUCCCGCCUCUGUCUCCUUCUUUCCUGCCUUCGCCUCCCAUUCCCCGGUUCUCUCUCUCUCCCCGUCCUUCUCUGCCUUUGUACACCUGCCUGACAUGUGUGUCUUUUCUUGACGCUGCUCCCCGUGAGGGGGACUAACCGUCAAAGACUCGACUUUUCUCACCCGGGCUCCUUCCUUCAAGUUGUGCUCCUUUUGGAAAUACCGUUUGGAAGAAAAGUGGUGCCGACCUCCGAAGAGAGGGAAGGGGCUUUGCCUGUAUUGUGCGGAUGCUGGUGUCAGACGGAACUGAUGUGGUCAUCCCAGCCUGGCAGGGCUGAUGGGCAGCGAAGGAGGCCCCGGAACCUUCCUUCAUACCCCUGAAGUGCAGGGUGUGUGUGGAUUAGACUUCAGAGACCAAUCGUUGGCUGGUGGAGGCUGGUGGAGGCUGCCCGAGGCAGAUAGGACACCUGCUUUCCAACCUUCCUGAGGACCCCAUACCCCCACCCUCCUCGCUGUCCAGGCACUGAGGAGAGAAAAUGUCCUCGCCCUUUAAACUAGAGCUUUCCAGAUUUGGGCACUCACUCUCUGCUUAUCACUCUGUCUUCUGUUCGUGGUACCUUGUCAGGUUGUUUUUGUUGUUUGUUUUGUUUGGCACUGAGUUGCAGAGCAUCAAUUUGUUCUUCUGAAAUCUGUGCAACACCUGUCUUCUGUGAAUGCUAUCAGAUAGUUUGAUUUUUUUUUUUUUUUUGGUAAUCCCAUUCACGUAAAAAUAUUCAGUGUGACAACUUGUGAAGCUUCCUUUAACUUUCAGAACUUGACUCAAUGUAUUUUUUUCCCCUUUGAGAUUAAAAAAAAAAAUCAACAUCUCUUCUCUUGGACUCAUGAUGCCAAAAAAGAAAAAGUCCAAAAUCAGUACAUUUUAAUAUUUAGUAGCCAUGUAGGAAAACAAACAGACGGAUUUGUGUUGAGUUACAGCCUGGAAUGGAAUGACAUAGAAAAGAGGGGGUUAAUAAUGUGUUGGCCUUCAGAGUCUUGCUAGUUGGCGGAUUCUUCAUUUCUCAAACAUGUCAACUUCCUCCUUCCCAUGGCUAACUCAGCUGGGGACUGCCAUCCAAAAUCUGUCUGCGUGUGGAAGGACUCCAGCACUUUUAGGGGAACCAGAUACAGUAAAAUCUUUUGGGAAGUGCACCAUUUUCUUUUCUCUCCUAACUUGCAUCCAAAUCUGAUUUCUCCUCAUGAAGAUGCUGCAUAAUUAAUUCUGAUAGUAGCAUAGUACAUGAACAAACUGUAAAAGCUGAAUGUGGAGGCUCAGUUAUGGAGUGCUCAUUUAGGCAAGGCAAUUUUGAAAGCUAAGCAGUGUAGUCUGUCUUUGGAAAUGACAGAACUGCAUUUCCUUACACUUUCUAUGCUUAGAGUAUUUGAUUGCAUGUAAAUUGGAUAUAGAGCAAUGCCUGAAACAGCAGGGCAGAGUCAAACCUACAGUAGAAGAGGGGACCCCCACAGGAUAUUGCACAAUGCCUCUGCAAAUGCCCUGGCUAACUGAGGUGCCAGUUCCAGGGCAGUCCAGGGUCAAAUAAUAGAGGUGGAAGGACUUUAGAGGUCAUUGAAGUUGAACAUCUACUGGUUGUUCAAAUUCCCUUCUACAAUCUUUCUGACAAAUGGUUGUCUAGCCCAGUACUUCCGUAAGACGGAACUCAUAUACUCGUUAAAAGAACUAGAUUUUCCCAGUCACGAAUGCCUAUUUUUAGAUGAAAACAAUCUCAGCUUUAUAAUAUUGAUGGUGUUUAGCUAAUCUUUUGUGUAGAACACUGAAGAGUUCUAGGUUGUGAACAGAAGAUAUGGGCCCCAUUGCUGGCUCUGUUGCUAAAUUGCAGUGUGUUCUCCAAGUAUCAAGACCUUCUUCGCCUUCGGUUUCCUUGUCUGUGGUAUUAUUAGGAGGGAUGACUAUUCUUUAGAGAAAUUUCUAGUUCACAUAUCUGUCAUUGUUAUAAUUAAUAACAAUGUAAAUUUAGCUUCUUGCAAAGUUAAUGAGCCAACGCUAUUAAGCAAUGAGGAGUUUGGAGGAAAGAACAGGCAUUGGUAGAUUAUAGGAUCAUAAUUUGUUGUUUGGGAGAUGUCCAGAAAUGCCUUGUAAUGUUGCUACUAACCAACCUUGGGCUAGUUACAUAAUUCUUCUAGAUCUCAGUUUCAUCAUCUGUGAAAUGUAUGGGUGACAAGAGCAGCUUUAAAAUUCUGAGUCUAUGAAUAAUUUGAGAAAAGAAAAUGUCACCAACAUUUUCCUGGCUCAAAGAUGAUUUUGGCACCCAUAUUAGGCAAACAUUAUCACCUUUGUUUUGGCAUCUGACAUUAGUGGCUGUGGUAUGAAUUUCUUAAAUGAGCCAUUUAUAAAACUAGAAAUUAACACUGUAUCUAAUUUUAAAAUUUGAGCAACUAGAGUCCCAAGUUCCAUUCUUUCUUCUAUGAGUUACCUUGUUUAUGAGUCUUAGCAUCGUUUAGAAAUUUUAAUGGUAGGAAAUGAAAAGUUUAUUCAGAUGGGAGAGUGGGGAGGGGUGGAAAAAGGGCUCAAGAACUGUCUGGCAUGCUUAGUGAGCUUCUGAGAGGCAAAGAUGUCAGCAUUUUCUUCUCUGGACCUAGAGGGCAAAGCUAGGAGUUGAAUGAGGAGUGCAGGGAAGAAAAUGUAGAGUUGAUAAUAUGGAAAACAUUCUCAUAAUAGGAAUUAUUUACAUUUCCUAUUACUGGAGGCAAGACAAGAGAGAUAUAUUUCUGAGAGAUGUACAGGGGAUAGAAACAUGCAAUGUGGGCAAUAAGAGAUUAAUUUAGAAAUAUGCAAGGCUCUAUAAUAUUAGUCUACUUAAGAGAAAUCACUGGAGCUAGAAAAGCAUUUAUCUCAAUGGGACAAGUAUUUGGGAGAAUCAUCAAGUUCUUGUUUUCACACUCUUAUUAUGAUACAAGUUCACUUCUAUCUAGCCCAGAGCCUGGAAUGGUCUAGGCUUGACGUUUAGCCAGAACCUUCAGAAAGAAUGGAGGUAAAGUUAUUGAUACGCUCAUUAAGAACCAAGACUAGAACCCUUUGCUAUUCUACCAGACUGACAAAUAAAACAAAAUAUUUGCCAGCAUAGUUUAAACAUAGUUAUUUUUCUAGCAGCAAGUUCUCUUAAUAGCACUAUAUUGACCAAUCCACAUUUCACUAUCUUGUUCACUGGGAUAACAUGAUAACUUAUCAAAUGCUUUAGAGAUAUUACAUUCAUACUGUAUUUCCAUACUUACUGUCCAAUUCAGUAAAUGCCCAUUAGAAGCUUAUUAUGUGCAAGGUAAUGUUAGAAGAUUUUGGCUAAACAUGUGGGGGUUCUUUUGUGUUUGAGUUGGUCAGUUGACUCUAAAUUAGUCUUCCUUAUAUGCCAUUCUUGCAGCACUGGCUAACUUUUGAUGCUGAGGAAGCUUUGCUGAUCCAAGUAAGGACUGACUUGGAAAAGUAUGCAAAUGAAAUCAGCCUUCACCCAGCGAUUUGAGUGCUGGAAUAGUUGAACAAAAUGGACUUAAAGCUUAGGGCUUCAGGUACCUCUGUGGCACUGGGAAUGUGGGGGGCGGGGUCUGAAAGAAGUCUUUAGGUGUAAAAAUCUGUAAGGUAAGUGAGUGUGUCAUGGAUUAUAAAAGGAUGCCAGGAAAUGACAAGUGGCCUAAAGAUAGUUCUUCAUUCAUUCAUCCAUUUAUUCACUCAACAAAUAGAUGUUGGAGUGUUGGUUAUUGUACCAGGUGUAGAAGAUACAGGAGUGAAUAAAAUAGAUAAAAAUCCCUGCCUUCAUAGAGUUUAUUUCAAGUAGUGGAGUUAGUAUUUUCUAGUGGAUUAUAUUAUAACUACUCUUAGUAGGUCAUAGGACCAGGGUAGGAGAAUACUUUGGGAUGGCUGAUAGCACUGGUGGGUAAAAUGACAGAAAAUACAGGGCAGAGUGAUCACAUGCAGCAUCCUUUAGGGGACUCCUAGCUGUUCUCUCCCAAGUGCAGUAUAUAUGUUUCAACUACUGGAUGAAUAGGAAGACAGGACAGAUGGAAGCAGACUCAGUUGGAAACAUUAUGUAAUGCUUCUUUCAGUUCUUGAAAACACUGACUUUAAUAAAUAAACAUUGAUGUGACUUGCAAAUACAUUAUGUAGAACUUUGGAGAAAUCAAUUUUGAAUAGAAAUUGGAGUCAUAGAAAUGACAUUAGAAGUUCAGCUAUUCACACUAGCCUUCACUUUAACUUUUUAAUGAAACAUUUUCAUUAAAAACAAUUAACAUUAUUUUCUAUUAUAUAUACUUUGUGCAUGUCAAUGAAAUUCUAAUAUUACAUAUUAUCUGCAAUAAAAACAGAAAAUUAAUGUGUUUUGUUUUUAUAAAAUUAAAAAUGAUAGGAUUUCAGAAAUGUGAAGAUUAUAAGGCUGUAUGCACAAUGCUGACCUGUAUAAAUCAACUGGGUUUGAAUUCUUGAAACUUGGAAUAGAACAUGUUCUUGUAGUUGCAGAAGCAUUUUUCCUCUAAUGAGAUAAACAGAUAUCAAAGACAGUGGGUCAUAAAUACUUUGUCAUUUUGUUCUCUAUAAGAAAAGCAAAGUAAGAGAUUUGGUAGGAAUUCAUUGGGUCUGCUUUUCACUCUGCUCAUGAUUUAUCUGCCUCUCCUGUUGCUUAUUUCCCAUGAAAUUAAUAGUCUGCACAGGACCCACCAAGUUCUACCUGACACAGAAAUAGAUUGAUGAUUUUCUUCAGCUCAUUUGUAGACCAAAGUAUAAUUUGUGUUGGAAUAAUUAUCUUCCAAGAGCAGAUAUAUCUAGGGAAGUUGAGAAACCAGCACCGUCUCUCCUUCUUGACCCAGUGGUUCACAGAUUGUUCUCGGACCUUCUCUUGGGUUAAAAGAUGCUGCUGGUAAAAGGGAUUCCUCAGUUUUGGGGGUUCUGGGGAUAUGAUUAAGACUUCGUUUUUCUUUCCCUCUUUACUUCUCAAGGCGAGUAGUGUCUGAAAUUCUUUGGGCAUCACUCUGUGAUUUAUGUUUAUUCAUUUUUAAAUUAUGUGCAUGGACUGUACUGACACAUACAUCAUAAAACAGACAAAAGCAAAUUUCGAAGGGAUGUGGUAAUACAUAUAUAUAACUAGAAGUUCAACCAUUUUCAUGCCACUGUCCAAAGAAUUUCAUGUGCACCCCUGGCAUGUACAGACCGCACUCUCAAGACUGCUUCUCUCACUGCUCAGAGCCAAGUCUCUCAUCUGAGCAGAGGAGGAGGGAUUUUUCCUAUCACAGCUGAAAUUCAUGGCGGGUAUCCCAGUGCGCUCUUAUAUCACACACAUUUAUCUUGCACAGGGGAGAGAAGAAGAUGCAUUUUAUUUCUGUACCAAUUCUGACAUUAGGCACAGUAUUAAAUGAGCCCUUUUUGAUUAAACAACUGCUAGCUCAUACUACACAACUCUUAAUGACUAGAUUUGUAGUUUUAGCUUGUUCCACAGUGUGCUGAGGCUGAACAUACCCAAGUGUGAUAUUCAAUGUUUCAACACAUUCUAUUGCUAACAUCAUGAAGGUUAUCUUGAAUAGAAAUUAAAUUCUUGCCACUCUGCCAUCAAAAGAAUAUACUUGCUUCCAUUCUUACUAUCUGCACACAGGAAUUGUCUUUUAAAAGUGAUUUAUAAACACAAAAGUGGAUGGUACUUUAAGUAGUUUAUGAUCAAAAUUGCCAGAAUCAAUGACAUUUUCAUUCACUAUGUUUCAUGGAUAACAUUUAGCAAUGGCCUUGAGGGGAAAAAAGGAAGAGUUUGCUAUGUCAUAGAAAGUUCACAUCCAAUUAUACCCGAGUUGCUGUGCUUUUUUUCCUUAGCUACUGAUUUUUCUUCUUCAGAUAGCAAAAAGAGCCCUCGAACCCCAUCAGGCAGACUGCUCGUAAUUAUAAUUGCAACGGUUCUUUUUUCAUUUUUUUUGAGACAGAGUCUUGCUCUGUCUGUCACUCAGGCUAGAGCUGAGUGGCACGAUCAUAGCUCACUGCAGCUUUGAAUUGGGCUCAGGUUAUCAGGUGAUCCUUUCACCUCAGCCUCCCAAGUAGCUGGGACUACAGGUGUGUGCUAGCACACCUGGCUGAUUUAAAAAAAAAACAACUUUGUAGAGAUGGGGUCUUGCUAUGUUUCCCAAGCUGUUCUCAAACUCCUGGCCUCAAGAGAUACUCUUGCCUUGGCCUCCCAAAGUGUUGGGAUUACAGGUGUGAGCCACUGGGUUUCCCUCACCCAGCGAGUGUCCUUGAUUGCUAUAAAAGAUCAGUUUUUGUUGGAGGAGCGUCUGGACAUUCCUUCCCAUUGAGAAAAUGUCAAUGCUAAGUGUGAAAUGCCAGGGGAUGGGAACAUUGAAGGAAUUGAGGUGGGUCACAGGGUUUUCCCAACAGUUAGCAAGAAUGAACUCUGCUUUCAUCUUUGUGUACAUCUGUAGUGCUGUGUGCUCCAGAUAAUCAGCUUAUAAUUACAGAUUAUAUAAUCACAGAUUUUCAGAUUAUAAUCACAGAUUAUUCAUGCCAGCAAACCACGACCUCAGAUUGGCCAUCUCUUCAUGCCCUGAGCCUUGGAGCAUGAGAGAGUCCGCCUUGGCCGUCGUCAUGAAGCUGACAGCCUUUGUUUGCUGCAGAGUCACGGGAAACUACAUGCUGCACCCCAUCUUUCUUGCAACUCCGCCAGAUAGCUGAUUGCAGACCCAACAGUAAUGUCAUGGGGACACCCAUCAGGGAAUGCAUUAGCAAGUGAACAAACGGGGACAAAUACAAACCAUAUUUAAGUUUCUGUUAUCUUUAAUUACUGAGGACACACUGAAUUAUUUUCUAUAACUUGCUGGAUGUCCUCCAGUGUUCAGACUUUUUAAUAUUUCGUUCAUAGGUAAAAAUCAAUCAACUCAUUUUUCCCCUAAGAACCUAAAGGAUGUAAUAUAUUCCCUUUUGGUUUCACCAAGUGAUUUGACAUUCUAUAGCUAGGGAAGAGACUCCAGAAAUGUAAGUAGGAAAUUCUGAGUGUACAGAUAAUUCCAGAAGGCUUAAUUGUCUCUUUACAACAGGUCACUCAAAUGCAAACCCACACCAUGCUUCCAUCUGCCUUGCAAAUAAGUACUAACUUGCACUCUUAAGGUCUGUUACAGCAGAACUAGCAGGGUAGGGGCAGUGGUGGAUGGGAGGCUAUACUGGGCUUGGAUCUCUUUUGUCUACAUUUCAAGGAAUUUUUAUUUGGUGUGGGGGAUGUGAGCACUUGCUUCACUCAACAAUCAUCAACAAAUGUUAAAAAUGAUUUUUUUUUAAACAGGAGGCUGUUUAGUGAAAAACAGGGGUGGUCCCAUGGGAAUGUGCUUUCCCUAACUAUACCCAGAGCAGUGAGGAAGGGGGUCUAAGUGAGUGGGGGCAGGCUGCUGGUUAACUUGAGUUUUAACACCUUUUUUUAAGUUCUCACAAUUUUGAAAGCUGCUUGUAGGAAAACUUCUCUUGGUAUUCAGACAAUGGAAGUUUGGUUGAAGGAAGCUACAACUUACAAGUAUUGGAAAAACAGAUAGGCUGAACUAAGGAGUGGCGGGAAAAGCAACAGUGACUGCCAACAUCAACGGUUCAAUAUUGUCUUUUUCUAAGAUACUUGAACGUGCAUGUUUAUAGCAGCACAAUUCACAAUUGCAAAAUCAUGGAACCGACCCAAAGGCCCAUCAAUCAGAGUGGAUAAAGAAACUGUGUGUACACAAUAGAAUACUACUCAGCCAUGAAAAGGAAUGAAUUAAGAUCAUUUUCAGUAACCUGGAUGAGAUUGGAGACUAUUAUUCUAAGUGAAGUAACUCAGGAAUGGAAAACCAAACGUUGUAUGUUCUCACUGAUCAUUGGGAGCUAAGCUAUGAGGACUCAAAGGCAUAAGAAUGAUACAAUAGACUUUGGGGACUUGGGAGGAAGAGCGGGAGUGGGGCGAGGGAUAAAAGACUACAAAUAUGGUGCAGUGUUUACUGCUCCAGUGCUGGGUGCACUAAAAUCUCACAAAUCACCACUAAAGGACUUACUCAUGUAACAAAUACCACCUGUACUCCAAUAACUUAUGGAAAAACAAAAUAAAAAAAAUUAAAAAAAUUUGUCUUUUUCUUCAGGUGUUUGAAACAAACAAAAAAGACACAAAGGAACUGUUUACUAUACAGCAGUACAAGAAAAAAUCCAGCCAGAAGAUACCCGCUGAAGAAGCAUCAAAGUCUUGUAUUCCUUUCUCUCUCUCUCUUUUUUUUUCUCAAGUUACCUUUUCUUUCUGAAAUUCAAGUUGGUAGGAGGAAAAUAAGCACGCGUAGAAUAAAAAAUUCAUAGAGUUGAAAGGAAUUUCAAGCAGUGAUUCUUACCUGAUUUUUAUACUAUAAUGUGGGUGAUAGGUGAUUUGCACUCGGGCUACAGACUCCUGUCAAUUAUCCACAAAACCUGGCAUACCAGCUCUAACUGCCUUCAUUUCUCUCUCAAACCAUAUUAUCAGAAUGCCUGUGAGCAAGGGGGAUGCUAUUAUCAGCAUAAUCUCAAAUGGGUUUUAAUUUAUGAGACAGAAUAUAUUGCUUGGAAGGAGUAGGCCCUUUGAUUUUUGUAUAGAAGAUGUAGGGGUGGGGGCUUCAUCCAGAUCAUGCAUUUUGAAGUGUUGGGGGUAUAUGGUGAGCUGAAGGAUGAGUGCUCAGUCCCCCAAAGUCAUCUCUAGGCACCACCACUGAUUUGGAAAAUUGGCAGCUGUAUAAAUAACUCAUUACCUACCAGUCCUCUGAACAGGUCCCAACACAUCUGAUUUGGGAAAGUUAAAAAAUAAUGACAGGAGAGGUUAUAAAAGGGCAGUUUUGUAUGCCAUACAAAUGUGACAGUUACUGAAAUAAAUAGGUCUGAGAGCCACUGAGAGGCGUGAAACAGAGUAGUUCCCCGUUGACUUAACCACCGAUACAGAUGAUUCUGCGGUAUUAUUUUGAUGAUGCCACAGGGGAAAGUGAGUGCUGCUUACUAAUAGGCCCCAGAUUGUAAUUUUGGAAAUCUGUGGCAUGGGUGUUUUUUAGAGCAUGUUUUUAUUUAUAAGUUAUCACACAGUUCUUGUUUUCACAUUCUUCUGGCUGUAUUUACAGGUUAAAAUGCCAGACAUUUUUUUUUUCCUGGUCAGGUAUUCAUCCAUACAUGCAGUCUUCUGGAGUUGUUAUUUAUUUCUUAAAAACGAUUUUCUUUUUUAGAGACAAGGUUUCAUUCUGUUGUCCAGACUGGAGUGCAGUGGCGCGGUCAUACUUUGCUGCAGCCCCAAACUCCUGGGCUCAAGUGAUUGUCCCACCUCAGCUUCUGGAGUAGCUAGGAUUACAGGCAUGCUCUACCAUGCCUAGCUACUUUUCUUUUUAAAUUUUUUUGUAGAAACAGGGUGUUGCUUUGUCGACCAGGUUGGUGUCAAACUCCUGGCCUCAAGCGAUCCUCCCACCUUGGCCUUCCAGUGUUGGGAUGAUAGUUAUUUCUAAACAAGGUCAGAUAUAGCAGUAUUUCUCAUUAGAUAUGAAACAUUAUAAUUUGGGUUGUGGGUGUAAUUUUAAAAUAUGUAGUUGAUAAAGUGCUUGAUAAACAUUUAUCCACUCACUUGGGUGGGCCUUUAAGUGCCAAAUAAUAGAAUACCCAAAUAAAAAUGGCUUAGCCUACAAGGAAAACGUAUUAUCUUGUGUAACAGGACGUUUGGAGAAAGCCUGCAUGUGGCUAGUUAAUUAAAGAGAUUCAAUGGUUUUGGGCUUUAGCAGACCCAAGGUAGGCAGUUUUGUCUUGAGCCAUGUCUCUACCUGGUCAUGACAGUUCUGUGAGUUGCUAGUUGUGAAUUCUGUGAGUGAGCUAGGAAACGGAAGAAGCCAGUCCCCAUUUUCCGAUGUCUUCUUUUACAAUAAAUGUAAUUUCCCAGAAGGCGUCCUGCAGACUUCCCACCGGUCUCAUUGGCUAGAAUUAUGUCACGUGACCAUUCUUAAAGCAAUCCCGGGCAAGUGGAAUGGACCAUGAUUUUCUUAGACCAAUCAAGCUUCAGCCCUGGGGCUGGAGAAAGGGCCCAGGCUCCCCAGGAAGCACUUGGCUGGCUGACACCUGAACAAAAUCUGGCUUUGGUCAGCCACGGAAGAGGGGUUCCAGAGAGCCACACAAGAUAGAGCCUGAAGCAGCAGGUGUGUUCAGGCGGCAGUCCCAUCCUGCCUAUGGUCAUUCCAUAGUAGGAGAAGACUGAGAAGAGAACUCAGAUUUUCUUCCAGCUUUUCCAGAUCUACCACUUUCUCCACAUACUGCCCUAAUAGACACAUGGAAGUGCCCUGAAAGCCCUGUGCUUUUCUGUUUGAAGAGCUGUUUGAGUCUCUUUAAUCUCUAGAGAUUCAGAGAUGGCAUGGUUGGUUCUAAGGAGGCUUAUUUAUAAUUGCACUUUUAAAAUUGAAGGUAAAUGUUCAAAAUUGUGCAUUCUAGGGAAUAUUAAUGUACUUUAAGAUCAGAAGGUGCAGUUGCUAUGAAUUUAAUACACAUUGGAUUGGAGAGCUUGGUGCUUCAGUGCUUCCUAUGUACAGCCUUUGUCCUCACUCUCGUCCCCAUUCCCCCACCCCUGGAUGUUCAGUGCCUCCCAAGAAGAGCUUCAUGGAGAGCAUUUUUCUGAAUAUCUCCCUUCACCCCCACUCCUCAAACCAGGUUCAUUUAUAGAAUCUGUUCAAGCCAGGCUAUGACUUUUUUUAACUUCUUGAUUUCUUGGAGGAAAACAACAACAACAUAUUUCAUUUCUAUCCUUUGACUGGCAACUGAGUGACCAUGAUUACAACUUCCCAGUGCAUCUAUAAAUAUAAUAACUUUGAACAAGAAAAUUAGCAAAUCACUCCUUGCUAUUGCCAGUGUCCUGGUGUGUUGAUAGUGGCGCGUGUUCAAAAUUAGAAAUUAAACAAUUCUAAUUUGAAGAAAAGCCACUUAACUCAUGUCUGUAUUGGGCUUUCAUUAUCUUUGAAAUUUCUGUGAAGUAUCAUCUGCUUUUGAAAUGACAAGCUGGAAGACCUGGGGAGGAAGCAGUUGUUCAGCAGUAUAUGUUUCUGUGUUUGGAGGAGUGGGAUGGACCCUGGUCAUCUCAGCAGGAAUGUUCAAGUCAAAACCUUUCCAGCAAACCUCAGGUUUCCUGUGCUAGGCUCCUCUUGGACCUCUCGUUCGACACCGAGAGACCUAUUUAUUACAGCUUGAUACUUCCUCAGAGCAGGAAUUAUGAAGCAAGAAAACAAUCUGAACUGUUACAGAUGGGCUGAGCUAGCAGGAUUUUAGCACAGAAGCCUCAGAAGAUGGUGUAAAGCCACAAGGUAUGUGGGUGGGCAUAUAUUUGGACCACCAUAUUGCAUGCCAACUUGUAGGUUCGACAAGAAAAAAAAAAAGCAAGCAAGCAGGCAGGAGAGAAAGGAAAGGAGAUAGGAAGCCCAAGAAGGAAGGCAGGAAGGAACAGAUGAGCAACUAUUUGGUGGAUCUUCAGGGAACCAUCUCCAUAGAUCUUGUUUCCUUAAAUAUCCAUUAGGUACAUUUAGCUUUCUAAAAUACAAUGUUAUGUCUUUCCUUUAAGUAAAAAUAUCGGAUAGAUUCCUUAAUAAGUUAAACAUAGAAGAACCAAAUAUCCCAGCAAUUCCACUAGUAGGUAUAUACCCCCAAAAGUUGAAAACAGAUACUCAGACAAAAACACUGUACAUAAAUGUUCACAACAGCACUAUUUGCAAUAGCCAAAAUAUGGAAACAAUCCAAAUGUCCAUCAACUGAUGAAUAGAUAAGAAAAUGUGGUAUGUCCAUACAAUGGAACAUUAUUCAGCCAUAAAAAGGAAUGAAAUACUGACACACGUUACAACAUGGAUGGACCUUAAAAACACUAUGCUCGGUGAAAGAAGUCAGACACCAAAGGCCAUAAGUUGUAUGAUUUUAUUUAUGAAAUAUACAGAUUAGGCAAACCCACAGAGACAGAAAACAGGGAGGGGAUAAUAGGGAGUGACUGCUUAAUGGGUAAGUGAUUUUCUUUUAGGUUUGUGAAAAUGUUCUGGAAAUAGAUAUUGGGAGUGAUUGCACAAUGUACUAAAUGUCACUAAAUCGUACACUUUAGUUAAGAUGUAAACAAAAAAACCCCAAAUCUCUGAUAAUUUCCCACUGCCUACAGCUACAAGUCUGAAUUUAGCAGGUCAUAAAAAAGCUUUUACCUUGUGGCUCCAGCUGCCUUUCUGGUUAUAUACCCAGCUACUUCUGCAUGAAAUCUAGGAUCAAGUCACAUAAGACCAUUUUCUAGUCCUUCAAUACACAUGCACUUUCGUAUCUCUGUGUCAUUGUGAAUACUGCUUCCUCUGCCUGAAUACCAUCCUCUCUUGUCCAUCUGGACAGCAUCUACUUUUCCUUGAAAGCUUAGUGCUAUUCUUAUUUCCUCUCUAGCUUUCCUUGCCUCUGUCCUCAGCACCUCUCUCAUUCCCUGCAGAAUUAAUUGCUGUAUUAACUGGGAUGCCAUUGUACUUUAUACAUACCUUUAUGAUAGCACUUUCUACAUUGUACUGUAUGGUUUCCUUGUUAAUUUUACAUCCUAUCUUAAGGCCAGGGAUGGAUACCAUCCAGGUUAGUAUUGGGCACAUGGCGAUCUGCCAUAGAAUGGUUGUUGAAAUUUGCCUUAGAUUGAUUCAAAUCACGGUCAUAUCUGACCCACUCUCUUCUCACCCACUUCAGUGUUUUUGUUGUUGUUGUUCAAUUCAAGGACAGGAGAAGUGAGAGUUAUUCUCAGUUUUCAAAGACUAAGACACUAAUUAUUAAUCCAAAGAAGAUAAGGUACUUGGUGUUAAAAAAAAAGUAGUAAUAGUGGUAGAUGGGUAAAAUGCUGACAUUUAUUAUACACUUUUUUUUGAAGUAUUCAAAAAAAAUCAGUGUAUAACUAACAAAGAGUGCAUCUUUAUGGAGAUUUUCCUCAUAAAAUGUUCUUAAUCCUUAAUAGAAGGAUUAUAUCAUUAUGUAGGUGUUUUUGUCUCUUUACUUAUCUCCAUAGGAAGUCACUACCUUCAAGAAACUCUUCCUUUGUCUCUGUUCUUUCACAGGACUUAGUAGGGCAGUUUUCAGAAGACGGAAACUCAAUAUAUUGGUCAUACUUUGCCAGGUUCAUUCUAUGUAUGUCCUUUUUCUGUUUUGGUUUAUUAAAUAUUCUUUUUCCAGUAAAACGGUUGCAAUUCCAGUUACAUACUUUCCUUGAUCAGAAAGCAGAAUAGCUGGAAUGAGUUGCUGCAAGAAAGACUCUUGGUUGCUGUCCUUCAUCAGGCUCUUCACUGAACCACCCUGCUGCUGUGUCAGACUUGCUACUAGGGAGAUUCCUGUAUGCUGAAAAAAGCCUGGAGAAUCACGUGGGGUGUGAGGGUGCUCUUCAGGCUCUUCAAGCAGAGGUGGCUCUUCAAGAGACCGGUGGUUUUACUGGCAUUCUGAAGCAAUCUUCCUCCUAACAAGUUGAUUUUGCAGUUUAUUGAGGUAUUGCGCAGCGAUGCACGGCCAUCAAGUACCACUUUUCUCAGCCCAUCCGCUUGCGAAACAUUCCUUUUAAUUUAACCAAGACCAUACAGCAAGAUGAGUGGCACCUGCUUCAUUUAAGAAGAAUCACUGCUGGCUUCCUCGGCAUGGCCGUAGCCGUCCUUCUCUGCGGCUGCAUUGUGGCCACAGUCAGUUUCUUCUGGGAGGAGAGCUUGACCCAGCACGUGGCUGGACUCCUGUUCCUCAUGACAGGGAUAUUUUGCACCAUUUCCCUCUGUACUUAUGCCGCCAGUAUCUCGUAUGAUUUGAACCGGCUCCCAAAGCUAAUUUAUAGCCUGCCUGCUGAUGUGGAACAUGGUUACAGCUGGUCCAUCUUUUGCGCCUGGUGCAGUUUAGGCUUUAUUGUGGCAGCUGGAGGUCUCUGCAUCGCUUAUCCGUUUAUUAGCCGGACCAAGAUUGCACAGCUAAAGUCUGGCAGAGACUCCACGGUAUGACUGUCCUCACUGGGCCUGUCCACAGUGCGAGCGACUCCUGAGGGGAACAGCGCGGAGUUCAGGAGUCCAAGCACAAAGCGGUCUUUUACAUUCCAACCUGUUGCCUGCCAGCCCUUUCUGGAUUACUGAUAGAAAAUCAUGCAAAACCUCCCAACCUUUCUAAGGACAAGACUACUGUGGAUUCAAGUGCUUUAAUGACUAUUUAUGCGUUGACUGUGAGAAUAGGGAGCAGUGCCAUGGGACAUUUCUAGGUGUAGAGAAAGAAGAAACUGCAAUGGAAAAAUUUGUAUGAUUUCCAUUUAUUUCAGAAAGUUUGUAUGUAACAAUUACCCGAGAGUCAUUUCUACUUGCAAAAGGAUUCGUAACAAAGCGAGUAUAAUUUUCUUGUCAUUGUAUCAUGCUUGUUAAAUUUUAAUGCAGCAUCUUCAGAACUUGUCCUGAUGGUGUCUUAUUGUGUCAGCACCAAAUAUUUGUGCAUUAUUUGUGGACGUUCCUUGUCACAGGAAGAUUCUUCUUCUGUUGCCUUAUUGUUUUUUUUUUUUUAAGUCUCUUCUCUGUCUUUGUACUGGAAUCGAAAUCAUAAGAUAAACAGAUCAAACGUGCUUAAGAGCUAACUCGUGACACUAUGCAGUAUUGUUUGAAGACCUGUUGUUCAACCUCUGUCUCUUUAUGUUAACUGGAUUUCUGCAUUAAAUGACUGCCCCCUUGUUAA